ACUGUCUGCUCAGGCUUCCAAAGCUACAACCUGCCAGCCUAUGCUCCAUACCUGCCCUGCGAGGACCUCCCAGUCUCUCAUUCUCGUCCUUGGAUUGGCCGCGAGACAUUUAUCCACUCUCCUUAGGCCUGCGCGAUGCAAGACGGGAGAAAAGGAGGGGCGUACGCGGGCAAGAUGGAGGCAACUACGGCUGGUGUGGGCCGGCUAGAGGAAGAGGCGUUGCGGCGAAAGGAACGGCUGAAGGCCCUACGGGAGAAAACCGGGCGCAAGGACAAGGAAGAUGGGGAGCCAAAGACCAAGCAUCUCAGAGAAGAGGAGGAAGAAGGCGAGAAGCACAGGGAACUUAGGCUGCGGAACUAUGUCCCGGAGGAUGAGGACCUGAAGAAGAGGAGGGUGCCCCAGGCCAAACCGGUUGCAGUGGAGGAGAAGGUGAAGGAGCAGCUGGAGGCCGCCAAGCCCGAGCCCGUCAUCGAGGAGGUGGACCUGGCCAACCUCGCUCCUCGGAAGCCUGACUGGGACCUCAAGAGAGAUGUGGCCAAGAAGCUGGAGAAACUAAAAAAGCGGACUCAGAGGGCCAUUGCCGAGCUGAUCCGUGAAAGGCUGAAAGGCCAGGAAGACAGCCUAGCCUCUGCAGUGGAUGCUGCCACCGAACAAAAGACCUGUGACUCCGACUGAGGCAUGCCCUGCCCCACCACUCGCCCAUCAGGCCUGUCCUGCAGAGGAUGGUCUUGGGCAGGGAUGGGGGCUAGGCUUGCCAUCACCUCCAGUUUGGCUUCUGAGCAGAGACUCCCUGCCCAUCAAGUCUGAAACCCCCAUGGAUGAGGUCAGCUCCUUGUCUGCUGGGUGGCCCCUGCCAUUCUGAAUGGAGGCAGAACCAGCAACAACUCUGGGCGUGCCUGUGUCUGCACAUGUGGAUGUACAUAUGUCUGUAUAUAUGUAUAUAUUUUGAACUUUCUAAAAAAAAAUCUGGAAAUAGAAACAAGUAAACCCCUGUGUGUGGCA